AGUAAGGAGCCGGAUGAUUGCCUCAGCAGGUGUGAAGCGUGUGCUUUAGUUUCGUGGGAGGCCUGGCAUCCCCGAGAGGGAGGGGAAAGGUAACCACUCCUUUGUGGAGGUCGCCAGGGUCAUUGUCGUGGAUUUGCACAGUCGGCUGGGCGGUGCAAUGGCGGAAAGAAAAGGAACAGCCAAAGUGGACUUUUUGAAGAAGAUUGAGAAAGAAAUCCAACAGAAAUGGGAUACUGAGAGAGUGUUUGAGGUCAAUGCAUCUAAUUUAGAGAAACAGACCAGCAAGGGCAAGUAUUUUGUAACCUUCCCAUAUCCAUAUAUGAAUGGACGCCUUCAUUUGGGACACACGUUUUCUUUAUCCAAAUGUGAGUUUGCUGUAGGGUACCAGCGAUUGAAAGGAAAAUGUUGUCUGUUUCCCUUUGGCCUGCACUGUACUGGAAUGCCUAUUAAGGCAUGUGCUGAUAAGUUGAAAAGAGAAAUAGAGCUGUAUGGUUGCCCCCCUGAUUUUCCAGAUGAAGAAGAGGAAGAGGAAGAAACCAGUGUUAAAACAGAAGAUAUAAUAAUUAAGGAUAAAGCUAAAGGAAAAAAGAGUAAAGCUGCUGCUAAAGCUGGAUCUUCUAAAUACCAGUGGGGCAUUAUGAAAUCCCUUGGCCUGUCUGAUGAAGAGAUAGUAAAAUUUUCUGAAGCAGAACAUUGGCUUGAUUAUUUCCCGCCACUGGCUAUUCAGGAUUUAAAAAGAAUGGGUUUGAAGGUAGACUGGCGUCGUUCCUUCAUCACCACUGAUGUUAAUCCUUACUAUGAUUCAUUUGUCAGAUGGCAAUUUUUAACAUUAAGAGAAAGAAACAAAAUUAAAUUUGGGAAGCGGUAUACAAUUUACUCUCCGAAAGAUGGACAGCCUUGCAUGGAUCAUGAUAGACAAACUGGAGAGGGUGUUGGACCUCAGGAAUAUACUUUACUCAAAUUGAAGGUGCUUGAGCCAUACCCAUCUAAAUUAAGUGGCCUGAAAGGUAAAAAUAUUUUCUUGGUGGCUGCUACUCUCAGACCUGAGACCAUGUUUGGGCAGACAAAUUGUUGGGUUCGUCCUGAUAUGAAGUACAUUGGAUUUGAGACGGUGAAUGGUGAUAUAUUCAUCUGUACCCAAAAAGCAGCCAGGAAUAUGUCAUACCAGGGCUUUACCAAAGACAAUGGCGUGGUGCCUGUUGUUAAGGAAUUAAUGGGGGAGGAAAUUCUUGGUGCAUCACUUUCUGCACCUUUAACAUCAUACAAGGUGAUCUAUGUUCUCCCAAUGCUAACUAUUAAGGAGGAUAAAGGCACUGGUGUGGUUACAAGUGUUCCUUCCGACUCCCCUGAUGAUAUUGCUGCCCUCAGAGACUUGAAGAAAAAGCAAGCCUUACGAGCAAAAUAUGGAAUUAGAGAUGACAUGGUCUUGCCAUUUGAGCCGGUGCCAGUCAUUGAAAUCCCAGGUUUUGGAAAUCUUUCUGCUGUAACCAUUUGUGAUGAGUUGAAAAUUCAGAGCCAGAAUGACCGGGAAAAACUUGCAGAAGCAAAGGAGAAGAUAUAUCUAAAAGGAUUUUAUGAGGGUAUCAUGUUGGUGGAUGGAUUUAAAGGACAGAAGGUUCAAGAUGUAAAGAAGACUAUUCAGAAAAAGAUGAUUGACGCUGGAGAUGCACUUAUUUACAUGGAACCAGAGAAACAAGUGAUGUCCAGGUCGUCAGAUGAAUGUGUUGUGGCUCUGUGUGACCAGUGGUACUUGGAUUAUGGAGAAGAGAAUUGGAAGAAACAGACAUCUCAGUGCUUGAAGAACCUGGAAACAUUCUGUGAGGAGACCAGGAGGAAUUUUGAAGCCACCUUAGGUUGGCUACAAGAACAUGCUUGCUCAAGAACUUAUGGUCUAGGCACUCACCUGCCUUGGGAUGAGCAGUGGCUGAUUGAAUCACUUUCUGACUCCACUAUUUACAUGGCAUUUUACACAGUUGCACACCUAUUGCAGGGGGGUAACUUGCAUGGACAGGCAGAGUCUCCGCUGGGCAUUAGACCGCAACAGAUGACCAAGGAAGUUUGGGAUUAUGUUUUCUUCAAGGAGGCUCCAUUUCCUAAGACUCAGAUUGCAAAGGAAAAAUUAGAUCAGUUAAAGCAGGAGUUUGAAUUCUGGUAUCCUGUUGAUCUUCGCGUCUCUGGCAAGGAUCUUGUUCCAAAUCAUCUUUCAUAUUACCUUUAUAAUCAUGUGGCUAUGUGGCCGGAACAAAGUGACAAAUGGCCUACAGCUGUGAGAGCAAAUGGACAUCUCCUCCUGAACUCUGAGAAGAUGUCAAAAUCCACAGGCAACUUCCUCACUUUGACCCAAGCUAUUGACAAAUUUUCAGCAGAUGGAAUGCGUUUGGCUCUGGCUGAUGCUGGUGACACUGUAGAAGAUGCCAACUUUGUGGAAGCCAUGGCAGAUGCAGGUAUUCUCCGUCUGUACACCUGGGUAGAGUGGGUGAAAGAAAUGGUUGCCAACUGGGACAGCCUAAGAAGUGGUCCUGCCAGCACUUUCAAUGAUAGAGUUUUUGCCAGUGAAUUGAAUGCAGGAAUUAUAAAAACAGAUCAAAACUAUGAAAAGAUGAUGUUUAAAGAAGCUUUGAAAACAGGGUUUUUUGAGUUUCAGGCCGCAAAAGAUAAGUACCGUGAAUUGGCUGUGGAAGGGAUGCACAGAGAACUUGUGUUCCGGUUUAUUGAAGUUCAGACACUUCUCCUCGCUCCAUUCUGUCCACAUUUGUGUGAGCACAUCUGGACACUCCUGGGAAAGCCUGACUCAAUUAUGAAUGCUUCAUGGCCUGUGGCAGGUCCUGUUAAUGAAGUUUUAAUACACUCCUCACAGUAUCUUAUGGAAGUAACACAUGACCUUAGACUACGACUCAAGAACUAUAUGAUGCCAGCUAAAGGGAAGAAGACUGACAAACAACCCCUGCAGAAGCCCUCACAUUGCACCAUCUAUGUGGCAAAGAACUAUCCACCUUGGCAACAUACCACCCUGUCUGUUCUACGUAAACACUUUGAGGCCAAUAACGGAAAACUGCCUGACAACAAAGUCAUUGCUAGUGAACUAGGCAGUAUGCCAGAACUGAAGAAAUACAUGAAGAAAGUCAUGCCAUUUGUUGCCAUGAUUAAGGAAAAUCUGGAGAAGAUGGGGCCUCGUAUUCUGGAUUUGCAAUUAGAAUUUGAUGAAAAGGCUGUGCUUAUGGAGAAUAUAGUCUAUCUGACUAAUUCGCUUGAGCUAGAACACAUAGAAGUCAAGUUUGCCUCCGAAGCAGAAGAUAAAAUCAGGGAAGACUGCUGUCCUGGGAAACCACUUAAUGUUUUUAGAAUAGAACCUGGUGUGUCCGUUUCUCUGGUGAAUCCCCAGCCAUCCAAUGGCCACUUCUCAACCAAAAUUGAAAUCAGGCAAGGAGAUAACUGUGAUUCCAUAAUCAGGCGUUUAAUGAAAAUGAAUCGAGGAAUUAAAGACCUUUCCAAAGUGAAACUGAUGAGAUUUGAUGAUCCACUGUUGGGGCCUCGACGAGUUCCUGUCCUGGGAAAGGAGUACACCGAGAAGACCCCCAUUUCUGAGCAUGCUGUUUUCAAUGUGGACCUCAUGAGCAAGAAAAUUCAUCUGACUGAGAAUGGGAUAAGGGUGGAUAUUGGCGAUACAAUAAUCUAUCUGGUUCAUUAAACUCAUGCACAUUGGAGAUUUAUCCUGGUUUCUUAGGAAUACUACUACUCUGAUUGUGUCUACUGAUUGGCUAUCAGAACCUUAGGCUGGACCUAAAUAGAUUGAUUUCAUUUCUAACCAUCCAAUUCUGCAUGUAUUCAUAAUUCUAUCAAGUCAUCUUUGAUUCCUGGACCUAAUAAAUUUUUUUUCCCUUUCUUUGGGUGUCCAAGAGAAAUGGUUUUUGCCAAACUCUUUUUAAAAAACAAAUUGUUGCUAUUUCCUAGAAGUUUCUGGUUUUUAAGAUGAACAUAAAAGUGUCAGUAUGCUUCUUUUAUGAGGUGUACUUUAUACUUUGAUGAAGGCUAAGGUGUACCUAACAGCUUUUUAUAGUAUAUUCAUUUAUGGAGUUAGCUGUAUUUUUUUUUAAAAAAGAAAAGUAGUAAAUUAGCAGCUUUUUUUUUUAAAUGAAGAGAACUUCAUGAUGAUUUAAAAGAACUAAUGAGAAUAUUUUGACUUGACUUCAAUUACUAAGUAUUUUGUAUAAAGAACAAAUAGGUCCUGCAUUUUAUAAGACUUUUUAAAGCUUUAAUUAUUCAACUAAGAACCAAUAAUGGCUUCUUCAAGGCUAAUAUCAAUAGUUUAUAAGCAGUAUAUUUCACCUACACUAAAUAUGGGCAUUUUAAAAGAAGAUUCCCCCCUUCCCCCCCAGAAAUCUGCAUUUACUAAAUUUGUCUUAAGUCCAAUUGUGUUUAAAGGUCAUGCUGGUCGGGUGUGGUGGCUCACACCUAUAAUCCCAGCACUUUGGGAGGCCAAGGUGGGCAGUCACCUGAGGUCAGGAGUUUGAGACCAGCCUGACCAACAUGGUGAAACCCCGUCUCUACUAAAAAUACAAAAAUUAGCUUGGCAUGGUGGCGGGUACCUGUAAUCCCAGCUGCUUGGGAGUGUGAGGCAGGAGAAUCGCUUGAACCUGGGAGACCGAGGUUGCAGUGAGCUGAAACCGUGCCAUUGCACUCCAGCUUAGGCAACAAGAGUGAAACUCUGUCUCAAUCAAUCCAUCAAUCAAUCAAUAAAAUAGAGGUCAUGCUGACUAUUA